AUUCCGGGUGCGCGCGGCUGUGGUCAGGUGGGCCUACCCAGCCACGCACCCGCCGCGGUCCCCUGGGCAGAGCUCCGGAGGCGCACGGCUGGCGGAGCGCACCCCGGGGAGGGCGCCAGAGCCGGCUGGGGCCCAGCUCAGGAAUCCAGACACGACCAAAUGACCUCUUCCUCUUUUCAACUCACGGAUUGAAAAACACACUAAACUUCCCGAAUAUAGAGGAACUGAAAAAUGUAUGGCUGUAGCAGGCGAACCGUGUGACUGCUUAGAAAACUGCACAGCAUCUGAUGAAAUUAGCGAAUAAGAACAUCAACCAUGUCUUACACUCCAGGAGUUGGUGGUGACCCCGCCCAGUUGGCCCAGAGGAUCUCUUCUAACAUCCAGAAGAUCACACAGUGUUCUGUGGAAAUACAAAGAACUCUGAAUCAACUUGGAACACCUCAAGAUUCACCUGAAUUGAGGCAACAGUUGCAACAGAAGCAGCAGUAUACUAACCAGCUUGCCAAAGAAACAGAUAAGUACAUUAAAGAGUUUGGAUCUCUGCCCACCACCCCCAGUGAACAGCGUCAAAGGAAAAUACAGAAGGAUCGCUUAGUGGCAGAGUUCACAACAUCACUGACAAACUUCCAGAAGGUCCAGAGGCAGGCUGCUGAGCGAGAGAAAGAGUUUGUUGCUCGAGUAAGAGCCAGUUCCAGAGUGUCUGGCAGUUUUCCUGAGGACAGCUCAAAAGAAAGGAAUCUUGUAUCCUGGGAAAGCCAAACUCAACCUCAAGUGCAGGUGCAGGAUGAAGAAAUUACAGAGGAUGACCUCCGUCUUAUUCAUGAGAGAGAAUCUUCUAUCAGGCAACUUGAAGCUGAUAUUAUGGAUAUUAAUGAAAUAUUUAAAGAUUUGGGAAUGAUGAUUCAUGAACAAGGAGAUGUAAUAGAUAGCAUAGAAGCCAAUGUGGAAAAUGCAGAGGUGCACGUUCAGCAAGCAAAUCAGCAGCUGUCAAGGGCAGCAGAUUAUCAGCGCAAAUCCAGAAAAACCCUGUGCAUCAUCAUUCUUAUCCUUGUCAUUGGAGUUGCGAUUAUCAGUCUCAUCAUAUGGGGAUUGAACCACUGAAGUUAUAAAGGAGCACACUGUCGCACUACAUUGUCUAAAUUAUGUAGGAAGAUUCCUGUAAUCAUGUUUUUUUAAUUAUUAUUUUAAAGCUAUUGUAUAAAGGAUGGUUCCCAUACUUUGUUAUUUUUAUUGGGGGGGUUGGGGUGGUUCCUUUGGAUUAAAUCUGAUAUUUUCUAAUACUGAAAGAUUUUCUAAAUGUCACUGCUGACAUAACUCCCUUGGUCUUCAAUUUAAUAGUUGUUAAGUUUUUGCCCACAUUGCAUAUGCCUUUCAUUUAUAAUUUAUUUACCCUGCUUGACUUAGUUUUGGGAAUUCGUAAAUUUAAAGGUGUGUGUAUUCUGUUUGCAUCUCCCUGUCACUGUGACACACCUAGAUGUGUGUUACUUCAAUUAAAAUUCUCAAAUUUAAUUUUGAUUUGCUUCAGCAGGGAAAAUAUUCUCAAUAAUGUAAAAUAAUUAAGGUCUAUACAUGGGUUGUAUUUUUCUGGUUCACAACAGCACAAAGUGUCUUUCAUUUUUUUGUUGGUUUUCUUUUAAGAUCUUUUUUACCCUGAAGUCGGUGAAUACUUUUCUAGUUUAUUUGAUACUCUUUCUGUGUAUAUAUUAAGCUUUUGCUGUAGAUUGCCUAGUAAAAUUACUAAGGAUAGGUUGUUUUUACAUAUGGUCUAUUUAAGUCUGAUGUUUACGGGGGAAAGUGUAGUUACUAAAAAUGUUUAACAUAAUUUGGAAGAAGAGUAUGAACAACCAAUACCAAUACCUAUUGCGUUUGGAUUCUUAAGACCCCAGUUUGUUAUUCCACUAAACUAGUUAUCUUAACCAUAUCAUCUGGUUUUGUGGGCCAUUAUUUACCUUCCCUUAUGUCUUAUAGAAUAAUGGUUAAUAUUUUUAGGUCAAAAUUACUUUUGGAAAGUAACUUUCCCACAAUUAACUGUUUUUGAGCACCUGACAAAAUUUAGUGUUUACCUUGCGUGCCAUUUUGUGUCAUCCUUCAUUAAAAAAGCAAUUGGAGGUUUGCCAGUUAUCUCACUUCCCUUUUUAAAUCAAUGUUGUUUUAAUGCACUAAUCUGAAUUCUGUAAAGAGGAUUAUCUUAGUUUAUACUUUGUAUUUUAUAAUGUUCUUGUAUAGCAGCUCGGUACUGAAGGCGGUGUUUAACUUGGCAAGCUCUGAGACUUCAAAUGGGAACAAAUAGUAAGUAGCUAAGUAAACCACAUCUUUGCAACCAAAAUAAAGAUGAGUUAAAAGGUAUCUGGUUAGGCCUAUUUCAUGAGGACUAUGCUCUGGUGGGACCACAGGUCACCUGAUACUUAGUGCUGUGCUGCCUGAAACCUCAGCAUGGAGACAUCACCACAUGCACUGUGGCCAUUCAGCAUCUUUCUGGAGCACCAGUUCACUCCAGGUUUUUAUUUUAGGGUGUCAUCGAUUUUACCUACUUUGUCAGACUGGUAGAAGUUGCUUUGCAUAUCAGAAAAACUCCAUUUUUUUCCACAAAAGGGAUUACAGAAAACUCUUUUGUGAGUGAGUGAUUGGAACUUAGAGACUCCUGUUGCCAGAAUCAGACUGCCCUAGAACAGAAUGGACAAUGCAGGGAGGAGAAUUCACACAAACAGCACCUGUUCUGAGGCCUGUGCCAGCCCACCAGGCCUGCUCAAAUGUGGUCUUUACUUCAAGUGCACAGAGGCACAUGAGGUUUCUGGUGAUAAACCAGCGUCUUACCGCUGUUUUAAAGUCCCAUCCCCAUGGCUUUCACAAUCAGUUCCGUUUUUUUUGCUGUACUUGAUAAAAUGUUUAUUCUCAUACAGGUCAAGUACAUUUACUUCUAUUCACAGUGAGUACCCAAUAACAACAAAAGCGCUUACAAAUUUGGGGGGCGUGAUUUUAGUACCUUUAUUUGAAGUGUAAUCAUUUUAAAUUAUUAUUAUUUUAACUGGGGCAGUUAUCAGUGGUUUAAACAGGAACUUUAGUGGCUUCAAUUUGUUUAAGAAACAUAUUAAGUUUGAGGGAAAAAUUUCCCAUGAAAUAUUUGGAACGUAAGAGUAGUAUUGAUUAGAGAAAAUUAAAUAAGAAACAUAGUAUGGUAGCCAAAUUUUUUAAAAAAUCUUGAACUUUUCUGUAGGUCAGUUUUAGAACUGCUGUGAAAAGUGAAGGUUGCCCUGUGGAGAUUAAAAUUAGAGUUGUUUUCAUAACUGACAGCAUGGUGAAUCCAUUUGAGUCAAAGUGAAGAAUUUCCUCAUCAAGUGACUAUACAUUUGUUUUUGUGUGCUCAAAAGAAAUACUCAAACACAGACUGAUAUUAACCAGCCAGGUAAAUUGAACGACAAUGUGGCAUUAGGUAUUUGGCUGUUUAUUGGUCGUUAAAUACUAUGGUUUUGCAAUAUGAUUGAUGGUAAAAGAGUGAUGUCAUAUUGAUACUAGAGUAGCUUGUUUUUUUAGUAGGUGUGGGACCAUCUCUUUUACAAGUGCAACUCAGUCUAGGACAGCCAUGGAUGCAGUGUCUGGAGUUGGACCCUCUGAGCCCGCUGGCUGCCCCAGUAGCAUCUGCAUUGGUGACCAAGGACACUGCACUUUGAAGAGGUCGCCACUGGGUUAUUUAGUGUCUUCACUGCUUUUGUUAAAAAUUGUAAAAUUUUGUACACAAAAAGUUGUGUUUUUGAAUAUCAAUUGUUUAGACACACCUACAAUGAUAAAUAAGUGCCUUUAAAGGCCCCUCUUUCCAUGAAAUACAUCUGUGGUUUAGCAAGGAAAGUACAAAAUAGUUUAUGUAGUUGGUAUAAUUUUUAUUUGUGUCUUCAUGUAGAAAAAAUGAAUGUCAUAAUAAAAUAUAAAACUUACGUAAAGAAAAUAAAGUCAUUGUCCACCUUAAUAGCUAAGGUCCACAAGGGUAACUUAUGCAGCAUUUAUUUUUUUUGAAAGUCAAAAUUGAAUUUAUUUCUUUCACAUGGCUGGUUUGCUGCAAUAUGAAGUUUCAGAAUGGGCUGAAGUAAGUUGAUUGAGGGAUUUGAGUUGAAUGACAUUUUCAAGUUCAUUUAAAUAUGAUAAAAAUUCAUUGGUGGUAAAUAACAUCUGUCUUUCCUGGAAAAAAAAAAGUUGUGUAUUUUCAUGAUUCAGUUAAAACAAAAAAUGAGCCUGUGAAUCCCAGGCCUUUUUAGUCCUCCAUAACAUUUGAACAGUUUGACUUGUCAGCAAAGAAAUACACUUAUCAAAUUUUAAACCAAUGGGAGCCUGAAAGUGUUACAGUGUACUGCUUCUUUGACAAAAUUCUGUUUAACAACUACCCUAACAUAAUUUAUAAAUCAAUUAAGAUAAAACCAUUUUUUUCUGAGUAUUUAGGAAUUUGUGUCCUCAAAAUACUGUGACAUGAAAGAUAGGAAAGAAAUUACCUGGUUGCCAGACAUGCACGAUUAUCUUUCCUCAUUUCAGCUGGAUUUUCCAAAGUCAGUAGAUUGGAUAAAGCAGCAUCUCAUUCACUGAGGUCACAAGAUAGGUAGGAAACUUCUUUAAUGUGAAUUUUGCAUAUUUUAACAAUUCAGUUAGAAAAACAGAAACCACUUGAUGGAUUAUAAGUGUAAAGUGUUUUAACAUAGGGAAUUAGACAUCAAAAGGGUGGGUGAGGAAGGUGUCUGCGGCCCCAAAGUGGGUGGAUCUCAGGAGCUGGCCCAGGCACUGCUGUGACUCUUGAGAACAUCCAGAAGGCUGUGCUGUUGGCGUGCAGCACUGACAGUGUGUCUCAGGGAGCUGUCCCCAGCUGUCAGCUGUUAAUAGCUCCAAAGCCAGUGCCUUGCAAGAGAUUUUGAAACUGCUGUGAAACUCAUGUCCUCUGCCCGCCUACACUUCUGUCUGCAGUGGCCUCUGAGGAAAGAUGGUCUCUCCUUUUCUCAUGGUCAACUCUCAACUUAGAACCAGAGACAGAAGGAGUUUGUGGGAAGUGUGGUUUCUGGUCUACCUGCACUGCAGAGGACAUUCUAGAAAGAGAAGUGAGUUGACAGUCUAGCAUAAUUGUGAAACAAACACUGAGAUGUACAGUUCAAACCACGUGAAGUGGAAGCCUCAGAAUUUUCCUCACUUUCAUUAAAGAUUCUUUGAUGGAAAAAUUUAGAAGCAUUGGCUCUAGAUGGUAAGCAAGUCAUUUUUUUCCAACCAAAAUAAAAAAUACAUAUACUAAGCUUCUGGGGCCCCAGGACUUAACACAGUUUCCUUCCUUCCUUCCCUUCUUCCUUCCCUCCCGUAGUAGUUGCUUAAUAAAUACUUAAUUUGGCACUUAUUUGGGGCCGGCUUUUUGCCAGGCUACUACAUGCCUGGGCAUAGUGUUCUAAGAGUGAACCAAAAGAAUAAGCUUCCUGCCCUCAGGGAGUUUAUGUUUUGUUAUUUGGCAUAUAAAAAGAACUUGGUGUGUUAAAAGAAGGGAAAUAGCUGUGUGAAAGGAAUGAGGCAAGGAAGAAAGGGAAUGUCUAAAUAUAAAUCUCCGUUUGGACCAGCCUCCUGUUUAUCCAGUUUUCCUUACUAAGUAACUGAAUUUCAUUUUCUUUUCUUAAUUGACAGACUACCAGAAAAUUGCUAGUUUUCUAAAGAGAAACUACUGAUUUGAGUGAUGAUCUGUGUGUAAUGGCUCCAAAAAGGAGCCGUUCUCUUGGUGGCAGCAGUUGGAUUCAGAGCUUGGGCAUCCUGAUCAUCAGGACAGACAUUUACAGGAUAUGUAUAGAAUUACUGCCCCAAAUAGAGGGCAAAGCACUAGACAGAAGGGUGAGAUCCAAGGGGAAUUUGGAAUCUAUAUUUCAUCAGAAUGCACUCAAAGCAAAAACAGUAAGUAUGCUCCAUAUAAAGAAAUGUUUCUUAAAAUGUUUUUAAUUUAACCCUACCCAUCCCUUGGCAAAUCUUUUUCUUUUAAAUCAAAUAGGAAUAAAGAAGAAAAUCUUCCUAUUGGCCCAUUUUCUCAUUAUUCAAAUACCAUAUCAAUACACCAAUUUUAAUUCUUUGUUUUUGUAAUCAUUUGGUUAACAUGAAUAUUAUGUAAUAUUUUUCUCCAAAUAAUCCUAAUUUUAAAUGCAGAAAUAGAGCUAAAUAACACACUAAAUAGGUUUUUGUAGACACUGUAGCUUCUGGCAAGUUUUUAAGAGGUUGGUCACUUAAUUGCUUAGAGUGGGAUUCCCGUAGGUUUUGUGUAGUGAUGGCAUUUAUGCUUAAAAUGUAAGUGGUGGAAGGCAAAACCAGAUUUCCUGUCCAGUCGUUACACGCACAACACCUCUACUUGUUGACGAGGGAGUUUUCUAGAACUGAAUUGAAUCUUUAAAUAAACUUGAAAGGGCAUUAAUUCCCACUUUGGCCAACCCAAAGUACAAAUUUUUAAGUGUUUACUGUAAGUAUCGUUAGGCAGUAGUUACUAACUCCAACACCUAAUAGCAUUGGUAGAAAGCUUAUAAAUGCAGUUAUUUAGCCUCGACUAAGAUUUUUCUGAUACCUAGUUUCACUUUUUAAUGCCCUCUGAAAGUUUUUUGAUCAGUUGUUUAAUGGGAGAUCUGAAAUGUUAAACUCAGACCAGAAAGAAGAGAACCUGUUUUCUAGAAAUUAGGUUUUUAAUCCAAGUAAGAUGCAAGCUUUUGCUUUUUUAAUAACUUGUAUAGCUAAAAACUUGACGGUGAAAAGCUCUCAGAUCAAAGCUGAUCCUUCUGUCAGUAAUGAUUCUAAAAAUAAGCAAGAUUUUAAUGGGGAAUAUAUUUUAUUUCAUUCUUAUCUCAAACCUAGGUACUGUGGUCGUUUUGAGUUCAUUUCGAGGCAUUUUCAAUGUGCCUCAGGCCACAUCCAACCUCUUCCCAGGGCCAGAUUUAAUGUUCAGCCUCAUAAAGGUUAUCAUAGUUUUAACAUUUAAGUACUAUUUUGCAGUGGGUAUAUACCAAAAUUUGCUAAUAGUAAGAUAACCUUAGUUAUAUAUCAUUCACGUUAGUUCUAUCUUGGAGGCAAUAAACAUUUCUUGUUCAAGAAAUUCAUGUUCUAUCUUGGAGGCAAUAAACAAACAUUUUUUGUUCAAAAUUAGGGCUACCCUAUUGUCCUUAUGUCUUUUCCUGAUCUGUGGUCAAACAUUUUUCUUAGUCAUUUAGAAAUUUUCUAUGUUGUUUUAAAUUUUCUUUAAAUCUAGAAUGGAGUAUGUGACCAAUACUUUCCUUUGGAAUGGUAUGGACAUUUGAAAUAGAGCCCAUUCUUUAUAAAGUAUAAAAUAUGUUUAAUGCUAGUAUUUUUAACUAAACUUUUGAGAAACUAGAUUCACAUGCUGUUGUAAGAAAUAAUACAGAGACCUCUUUCGUGUACCUUUCACUUUGUUUCCCACACAGUGAACAUCUUUCAAAACUGUCAUACAAUAUCAUACCCAGGAUACUGACACUGGUAUAGCUAAGAUAGAGAACGUUUCCACACAGAACUUUUUCUAGCACAGGGAUCCCUCAUCUUGCUUUUGAUGACCAUACCCACUUCACUCCCAUCCCUACUCCCUUCUUAACCCUUGGCAACCAUAAUCUGUUCUCCAUUUUUAUAGUUUUUUUUUUUUUCAUUUCAAUAAAGCUGUAUAACUGGAAUCAUAAUAAUAUGUAACCUUUUGGGAUUGGCUUUUUUUCAUUUAGCAUGAUUUUCUGGAGGUUAAUCCAGCUUAUUAUGUGUAUCAAGUCUAUUGACAGGUACUUUUUAGUGUGAAUAGAAUCCCAUAGUAUAGAUGUACCACAGUUUGUUUAACUGUUCACCUGCUGAGAGACAUUGGGCCAGUUUUUGGCUACUAUAAAUAAAGUUGCUAUAAACAUUUGUGUACAAGUUUUUGUGUGAACAUAAUCUAGUUUUCUGGGUCAAAUGCCCAGCAGUUAUAUAGUAGUUGGGUCAUAUAGUAGUUGAAUGUUUAGUUUUUAAGAAAUUGCCAAACUUAUACCAAGUAGCUGUACUAUUUUAUAUACCCACCAGUGGUGUAUGAGUGAUCUAGUUGCUUCAUGUCCUUUUCAGCAUUUGGUGGUGUCUCUUUUUUAUUUUAGUCAUUCUGAUAAGUGUAUAGUGACAGCUCAUUGCAGUUUUGAUUUACCAUUUUCCCUUCGCUAAUGGCAAUGAUGUUGAGCAUCUUUGUUUCAUAUGCUUAUUUGCCACCUGUAUCUCUUCUUUAGUGACAUGUUUCUUCAUGUCUUUUCUAAUUGGAUUUUUUUUCUGUUGAGUUUUGAGGGCUUUUAAAUAAUGUGUGUGUGUGCCUCUGUGUGUGUGUGUGUGUAUUUUUUUCUAGAUACUAGUCCUUUGUUGGAUGUGUGAUUUGCAAAUAUUUCCUCCCAGUCAGUAGCAUGUCUUUUCAUUUCUCUUUUCUGGGCCUUUCACAGAGCAGAAGUGUUUAAUUUUGAUGAAGUCCACUCUAUCCAUUUUUCUUUUUAUGGAUCAUGCUUCUGGUAUCAAGAACUUUGCCUCUCUCCUUAGAUCCCCCAAAUUUUCUCUUUUAUGUUGUUUUCUAAAAGUAUUAUAGUUUACGUUUUACUUUUAAGUCUAUAUUCCAUUUUCAGUUAAUUUUGUAUAAAAUGUGAGACUUAGGUCUGGGUUCAUUUUUUUUGUUGUUGCCUAUGGAUAUUCAAUUACUCCAACAUGAUAUUUGUCGAAAAGGCUCUUUUUUGUCCAUUGAAUUGUUUUUGCACCUCUGUCAAAAAUCAGUUGAGCAAAAAUGAGUUAAUGAGAAAUCAGUUGGGCACAUUCGUGUGGGUCUAUAUCUGGGUUUUCUAUUCUUUUCCAUUAGACUAUGUGUCUAUACCUCCACCAACACCAAAAUCUUGAUUACUGUAGUAAGUCUUGAAAUCAAAUAGGCUGGUUUAUUCCACUUUCUUUUUCAAAAUUGUUUUAGCCACUUAGUUCCUUUGUCUUCCCGUAUAAACUUUGGAAUAAUCUUGUCUGUAUCUAUUCAAAUAUCUUACUGGGAUUUUGACAGGAACUAUGUUAUACCUAUACAUCAAUUUGGGGAGAUUUGACAUCUUUACCAUGUUAAGCCUUCCCGAUCAUGAUCACAGGAUCACUUCACUUCAUUUCAGUUAAAUUUUGUUUUCCUUCAUCAGUAUUGUGUGGUUUUCAGCAUACAAGGUCUGUACAUGUUUUGUUAGAUUUAUACCUAAGCAAUUUAAUUUUUGAGAGAGAUUGUAAAUGGCAUUGUAUUUUGAAUUUCCUGUUCACAUGUCUAUUCUAAGUACAUAGAAAUAAAGUGAAUUUUUCUAUUUUGUAUACUGAGACCUUAUUGAGCCCACUUACUCAUUUUAGGGGAUUUUGAUUGAUUCCUUGGGAUUUUUUUUUUAUAUAGAUAGUCAUGUCAUCUGCAAAUAAUGAAUAGUUUUAUCUCUUCAUUUCUGACCUAUAUUCCUUUUUUUUUUCCUUUCAGUCCCUUAAUGCAGUGGGUAGAAAUUCCAGCAGAAAUAAAAGCAGUGAGAGUAGAGAUCCUUGGCUUGUUUCUGGUCUUAGGCAGAAAGGAUUCAGUGUUUCACCAUGAAGUAUAAUGUUAGCUGUAGGUUUUUAAAGUAGAUGCUCUUGCUAAAGUUAAGGAAGUUAUCUUUUAUUCCUUUUUUUCUGCAAGUUUUUAUUAUGAAUUUUAUGUUGAAUUUUGUCAAAUGCUUUUUCUGCCUUAAUUUACAUAAUGCCAUUUUUCUUCUUUAGCCCAUUCAUGUGGUAGAUACAUUGAUUGAUUUUUGAAUGUUGAGCCAUUGUUACAUCCCUGAGAUAAACUCCACUUGGUCGUGGUGUAUCUUUGUAUAUAUAGCUUAAUUCUUUUGGCUAAUAUUUUGUUAAGGAUUUUUGCAUCUGUUUUAAUGCGACAUACUGGUUGGUGGUAUCAGGGUAAUACUAGCUUCAAAAUGAACUGGAAAGUAUUCCUUUCUCUUCUGUUUUCUAAAGCGGAUUGUAUAGAAUUGGUGUCAGCGCUUUUUAAAACAUUUGAUAGAACUUUCCAAUGAAAUCAUCUGGGCCUGGAGAUUUUGGGGGAGGGAGUUCUUUUUAUUGUAAUUUCCACUUUUACAAUAGUUAUAUGGCUGUUUAAUUUAUCUAUUUCAUAUUGAGUUGUGACAGUUUGUAUUUUUAGAUGAAUUAGUCCAUUUCAUCUAAGCUCUCAGAUUUAUAUGUAGAGUUUUUGGUUGUAUUUUUUGUUAGACUUUUGAUGUCUGAUAUUCCAAAACUCCUUCAUUUAUCAUUUCCUUUCUGUUUAGAGCACUCCUUUAGCCUUAUUAUUAUUAUUGUAGUUCCAUUGGCAACAAAUUCUCUCAGUUUUCUUUCAUCUGAAAAUGUCUUGAUUUUCCCUUGAUAUCUGAAGAAUAUUUACAUUAGACAUAGACUUGUAGGUUUAUAGUUCUUUUCUUUCAGCACUUGAAAAUUGUUCUGCCACUUCCAGCCAAGAGGGGUGGCUCACGCCUGUAAGCCCAGCACUUUGGGAAGCCAAGGCGGGCAGAUCACUUGAGGUCAGGAGUUUGAGACCAGCCUGGCUAACAUGGCGAAACCCCGCCUCUACUAAAAAUACAAAAAUUAGCCGGCAUGGUGGUGCACAUCUGUAAUCCCAGCCAUUUGGGAAGCUGAGGCAGGAGAAUCACUUGAACCCGUAGGCGGAGAUUACAGUGAGCUGAGAUCGCACCACUGUACUCCAGUCUGAGCAACAGAACGAGACUCCUUGUCAAAAAAAAAAAAAAGGAAAGAAAAUUUCAUGGUUCCCCAUGAGAAAUCCAGUUUUUUAAAUUGUUUUGGUCCCUAUAGAUAGGUGUCAUUUGUCUUUUUUCUUUUUCUUUUUUUCCUUUGUGUUUAGUUUUUAGUUGUUUAACCAUGAUGUAUCUUGUAGAUUUGGGGGGUUUAUUAUAUUUGAGGUCUUCUCACCAUCUAUAUGUUUAUGUCUUUUGCCAAUUUUGGGGAGUUUUCAGCUGUCAUUUUUUUCAAGAACUUUUUCAGUCUUCCUUCUUUCUUCUUUCUUUUGAGACUCUGAUGACACAAAUGUUAGAUUUAUUGUAGUUCCGUAAGUCCCUGAGGUUCUGUUCAUCUUUGUUCUGCCUGUUUUCUUCUGUUGUUCAGACUGUGUAAUUUCUAUCAUUUUAUCUUCAGAUUUAUUCAUUCUUUCUGCAGUAGCUUCCAUUCUGCUAUUGAGCCUAUCAAUUAAGUGUUUCAUAUUGAUUCCUGCAUUUUUCAAUUUUAAAAUUUCUGGCCCUUUACCGAAAAUGUUGGUUGACCCCUGGAGUAUAAACCUAUACUAUAGAAGAGAGUAUCAAUUUUUUUUUUUUUGAGAGGAUCAAUUUAAACAAAAGUUGGUCUCUUUAAAUAAAUAAAGUACACAUAACUUGGUGAAACCGAUUUGGAAAAAAACAGAAGACAUAAAAAAUUUAGGAAUGAAAGUACAGAUAAAUAACCAAACAUAGAUUUUAAAAUAAUAAGACACUAUAAACAACUUUAUGCCAAUAUAUCACAAAACAGAAAAUGAAUAAUUUAUAUGAAAAAUGCAAAUUACCAAAAUCAACUACGAAGUAGAUGAUUUCUGCUUCCUGCCAUAUGGUUGACUAGGUAUACUCAAGGAUCCUCCUGCUAAAAUACAGUUAGUUCUUGGAUAAAAUACAACACACAUAAUAUUAGUUCAUUUCCUGGCUCAUUAGAAAGAAAGAUAAUCACUAAAGGCUAUUACCAAUGAGAGUGGGCUAAAAUUAAAGUAGUUGAGAAACAGGAAAACUGUGCCUCUGAGACUUAAGCCAUGGACUCCAGGCAAAGUAAAGAAAGUGAACCUAAGAUUCCUUCAUAAAACCAGGAAUGCUUUAAAGCAUUAAAGUAGUCCUAAGUCAGUGGACUCUGGUGGUUACUCUAAGAAGUGGAUGAAAAUCCCCUCCGAAGGAAAGCCUCCCUAAUUAAUGCUUCUAGAUUAAUCAAACAUGCAAGGAAACACACCAUUUGCAUUGAGAAACAGUAGAUUUAGAUAUUCAAGGAAUUCAGGUAUUGCAAUUAGCAGAAGUAGAAUAACAGUUAUAUGUUUAAAUAAUGUAUGAAUUAAAACGAACAUGAAAUGAGAGAUGUGUUAAAAGGCAGAUAUUAAAAAGAACCAAAGACAACUUAGGUAUGAAAUUUAAUUAUUGAAAUAUAUAACAUAAUGAAUGGUUUAAGAGCAGAUUCACCACAACUAAAGGAAUUGUUGACUAUCAAGUUUUAACUGAGGAAACAACAUAUUGCAGCAAAAACAGGUAAAGGGAUAGAAAAUAAGAAUUAGAGAUUAUGAGACCUGAAGGAUAGAAUGGGAAGGUUUAAUAUGUGCUGAUUGGAGUCUAAGAAGUAAAAAAUAGAAAAAAAUUGAGGUAAUUGCUGACAAAUUUCCAGAGCUAAGAAAAGCCUGGGACCUGGUAUGGUGGCUUAUGCCUGUAAUCACAGCAUUUUGGGAGGCCAAAGCAGAAGGAUCACUUGAAGCCAGGAGUUUGAGAUCAACCUGGGAAAUGAAGCAAGAGCCCCCACUCCAUCUCUACAAAAAAAAUUAAGAAUUAGCCAGAUGUGGUGACAUGAACCAGUAGUCCCAGCUACUUGGGAGGCUCAAGUGGGAGGAUCACUUGAGCCCAAGAGUUUAAGACCAGCCUGAGCAACAUGGUGAAACUCCAUCUGUACAAAAAAUACAAAAAUUAGCCAGGCAUGGUGGCACACACCUGUGGUCCCAGCUACUCAAGAGGCUGAGGAGGGAGGAUCACACGAGCCCAGGAGUUCAAGGCUGCAGUGAGCUAUGAUGGUGCCACUGUACCCUGUCUAAAAAAAAAAAAAGUGGAUCCACAUAUACAAGAAGCAAAAUGUAUAUCAACCAGGAAAAGGAAGCCAAUGUAUAUUCAUUAUACUCAAACUUCAGAACAAUAAAGGCAAAGAUAUCUUAAAAGCAGCCAGAAUAACUUAUCCACUUUUAAAGGAAUAACGAAUUGACAGACCUUUUUUUUUUUUUUUUUUUUUUGAGACAGAGUCUUGCUCUGUCACCCAUGAUGGAGUGCAGUGGUGUGAUUUCUGCUCACUGCAACCUCCAUUUCCCGGGUUCAAUUGAUUCUCCUGCCUCAGCCUCCCGAGUAGCUGGGAGUACAGGUGUGCGCCACCACAACCUGGCUAAUUUUUUUGUAUUUUUAGUAAAGACGUGAUUUUGCCAUGUUGGCCAGGCUGUUCUCGAACUCCUGACUUCAGGUGAUCUACCUGCCUUGGCCUCCCAAAAUGCUGGGAUUAGAGGCAUGAGCCACUGCACCUGGCCAACAGUAGACUUUUCAGUGCCAAAACUGGAAGGCAAAAGACAGUGGAAUAACAUCAUUAAGGUACUGAGAGAAUAACUCAAUAGAAUGAGUGCCCAGUGAAAUUAUCUUUCAAAAUCAAGGGUAUAUUAAAAACACUUUUUUCUCAAAAUGAGAAUUUACAAACAAGGGACUUUCACUUAAGAAUAAAGAUGAAUUUUAGAGUACAGCAAAAUGACUAGGAGGAAAGUCUGAGAUGCAAGAAGGUAUGGUGAGCUAAAAAAUCAGUAAUCAUGGGAAAUGUAAAUAAAUACUGUCUAUAUUAAGAAGUAUUUACUCUGUGGAGUAAAAAAGAGCGUAAUUAAAAUACUAGCAACAUUUUACAUAACUCAGGAAAUGUAUAUGUGGGGAAAGUGUCCGGGAGCACUUAGAAGUUAGUGUGAGUGCUCCAAGAUCCUGAUACUCUUUAGGAUGGAAGUUAAGAUAAUGAAUGACUUUAGAUGUUGUUAAUCUAAGUACUUAACAGAAAAUUUUCAGAUAACCUUUAAAGAAUAGCAAUACAAUAUAACUUUCAAACCAGUAGAGAGGAAACAUUCUGAAAUAAGGGAAAAACACUUUAGAAAUCCCAACUUUGAUAGACCACAAAAAUGCAAGAAGGAAGAAAAAGCAUAGAAAAAGCAAAGAAAUGGCAUAGUAUAUAAUAAAUGGUUACAAUAAAUAUAAAUUGCCUAUCUCACCAGAUUAAUAAAAAAAAAAGUCUACCUUGUUCAAUAUAUACAGUUUACAAAAGACAGUACAAGGACAGAGAAAGACAAAAAGUAGAAUUAGGGAAAAUAAAACAAGCAAAUAUACCUGGUUAGGAUAGCUGUAUCAGUAUUAGCCUUACAAAUAUUAAAGUGAAAAGCAUUAAUAAGGAUAAGGAGACUCUCAAAAAUAAUAAAAAUUUCAACUGAAGUAGGUAUAACAGUUCUAAACAAAGUUAUUAAAGUAAAAAUGUAGAGGGCAAAACGGAAAAAAAAACUAUUAUGUUGUAUUUGAAGUCACUCAAUUUUUAGCUCGAGCAGCAAAAAAGUAAAUAGAACAACAUGGUAACCAAAGUUGAUUCAAUUAAUACAUAAAGGAUCAUGUUCCCCCAAUUUAGAGCAUGUGCAUAUUUCUUAAGCAUGUAUAAAAGAUUUAGAAGGAAAAUGAUAAAGGAAUGUUUUGGGGACCUCUGAUAGGGAAAGAUUUCUUAGAAAAUCUGCAAAAGAUAUUAACCAUAAUCUACAUAAAGUCAACUGUUUUAUUUCAAGCCUCUCUGGAAAUAGUUUUGUUGACUGAUAAGAAACGCUCUAUGUCAGUCAGCUAAUCAAUGUCUAGUGAGUCUAACUCUUUCCACUACACAGUAAGUUCCAUCUUAGGGUGUUUUACUUAAAAGCCUGGUGUCAAAUGUUACACGCACAAAAACUUAUUAGUAUCUUUUUAACCAAUGUAUCUUAGGAGAUACGGAAUUAUUUCUAACACACUGGUUGUAUUUACUAAUUUUCCGCUGAGCCAUCAUAAAAAUAGAAGUCACAUCGUCACUAUUUCUUGCUUGUCCAACCCAGUGUCUAUGGUACCCUCGGCAGUUAUUCAUGGCUCCUAGGCCUUCUUUUAGAGUACUGUCUCUCUUCUAUUGGCUUUGGAUGGAAUUGACUCCAUCCUAACUGCAGAAAUGAUAGGCACUGCUUUACAUAAAUCAGUCAGCCUAAUAGCAUUCUUUUUGCCUCAGAGAUUGGUUCAGAGAUGGGGAAAAACCCACUCUAGGCAAUCAGCUUGUGACUUACUUUCCUCCAAUUGGUGAUCCAAUUAGGGCAGUGUGUGGAAUGUGCUGCUCUGUAUGUGCAGCCAGAUGCUCAUGUUCAUAAAAAACAUUUUAAUACUGUGAUGGAAGAUACAGCUUCGAGACAAAGACACAAGCUUGGGUAGAGUCAUUCAUUCAUUUAGUAAGCAUUUGCUGAGUGCUUAAUAAAUGCUGGGCCCUGAGAAAAAGCAAAAUCUUAUUCAGCACAUUCUGACAUUGGGGACAAUGCGAUAGUUGAUAGCUUCCACACUUAAUUAGAAACAAAGAUUAUCUCUUAAAACCUCAUUCUUGUAUCUAGGAAGACUUUUGUUUUCCCAAUCAGAAAUUGUGGUUCCAGAAAAAGAACAAGACAAUGAAAACAUUGUAUAAAAGGUUUCUUUCAAACUUUUUUCAAUUGACAGUUUUUCACCCCAAUCAUCUUGAUGCAGAGAGGCUUCAGAAACACAAGUGACUCUGUGUUCAGACCAAGUACUUGGCCUCGAGAAGAUGAAUGAUCAGACCAACUCACCAUAUGAUUAUAAGGGUCAGGUAGUUUAAAAAGAAAUUACAAUCUGAAUUGAACCAUGGAUGAACAGUGUUGCUAUUGAGCUUCGAAUCCCAGCUAAUAAGCAUAACCUUGUAAAGAGAGGUUACUGUUUGGGAAACUGCAUGUUCUUGCAGGAGGGCAAAGCUUUUGCAAUAUAAAUAGUUGUAAGGGUACUAGCUUUCAUCUUUAAUACCUUAACCCUCUGUGUUUAGAGUUUUUGUAUCCAGGGCUGAAUUGAGAAUUUUAGAAACCUUGAACACUGAAGAGAUUGUAAUAACAACCCCAUGUGUAAUUUAUAAAAUCUUCAAAAGAAAAUUUACUUUUUCAAAAUGUUAUAAAACUCUGAAUACUGAAAUGAAAA